ACUCACUCCCCCUCCACCCAGAGAGCAGGACGGAGGUGUGAACUUGAGCCAGACCAGAAGGAGCUCGAGAGCGGCCGCAGGACAAGCCCGAGGAGCAGGCGGGCGCUCCAGGGGAAAACCACGCACAAAACCUUCUUCAGAGAAAAGGGAAGCUCCAAACCUGACUGAGACAAACGGAGGCUCUUGAAAUAAAAAGAAAAUACCGCAGGACAAACAGCCUCCCGUCCCCGGGCGCAGGUCGCGGUCACAGUGGUGACCUGGGAUUGCUUUCCCAGGACUGCGAGUCGGGUUUGGGUUUCUCCUCCCUGCAUUCCACAGCUGCUCUGGUCAUCGCAACGUGUUUAUUGAUCACUGAAGAAUCUCAAGUUUUGAGACGAGGAAGAAACACCCAUUAGGUCUCCAAGACAGCUGUGUUUCACAAACUUUAAGGAGACAGAAAUUUUCUCCCCUGGAACCUGUGAAAAUGUCCCUUUUCCAAGGAAGUGAAGGUUAAGAGGUCCCGUUCUCACAGACCCUCAGGAAUUUCACUUGGCUCCGAGCUUUGACCUCCGAGAGAGCCAUGGAAAAGCUGCUGCGGCUGUGCUGCUGGUACUCCUGGCUGCUGCUAUUUUAUUACAACUUUCAGGUGCGUGGCGUCUACUCCAGAUCGCAGGACCAUCCAGGAUUUCAGGUGUUGGCGUCUGCUUCCCAUUACUGGCCACUGGAGAAUGUGGAUGGGAUCCAUGAACUUCAGGAUACAACUGGAGCGUCCCGAACCCACAAGCUCACUGUGCUUCCUUCCCGUAAUGCUACUUUUGUGUAUUCCAAUGAUUCUGCCUACUCAAAUCUCUCUGCAACUGUAGAUAUUGUGGAAGGGAAGGUCAACAAAGGCAUUUACCUGAAAGAGGAAAAGGGAGUCACGCUUCUCUAUUACGGCAGGUACAACAGCUCCUGCAUCAGCAAGCCAGAGCAGUGUGGCCCUGAAGGGGUCACGUUUUCUUUUUUCUGGAAGACACAAGGAGAACAGUCUAGACCAAUCCCUUCUGCGUAUGGGGGACAGGUCAUCUCCAAUGGGUUCAAAGUCUGCUCCAGCGGUGGCAGAGGCUCUGUGGAGCUGUAUACGCGGGACAAUUCCAUGACAUGGGAGGCCUCCUUCAGCCCCCCAGGCCCCUAUUGGACUCAUGUCCUAUUUACAUGGAAAUCCAAGGAGGGCCUGAAAGUCUACGUCAACGGGACCCUGAGCACCUCUGAUCCGAGUGGAAAAGUGUCUCGUGACUAUGGAGAGUCCAACGUCAACCUCGUGAUAGGGUCUGAGCAGGACCAGGCCAAGUGUUAUGAGAACGGUGCUUUCGAUGAGUUCAUCAUCUGGGAGCGGGCUCUGACUCCGGAUGAGAUCGCCAUGUACUUCACUGCUGCCAUUGGAAAGCAUGCUUUAUUGUCUUCAACGCUGCCAAGCCUCUUCAUGACAUCCACAGCAAGCCCCGUGAUGCCCACAGAUGCCUACCAUCCCAUCAUAACCAACCUGACAGAAGAGAGAAAAACCUUCCAAAGUCCCGGAGUGAUACUGAGUUACCUCCAAAAUGUAUCCCUCAGCUUACCCAGUAAGUCCCUCUCGGAGCAGACAGCCUUGAAUCUCACCAAGACCUUCUUAAAAGCCGUGGGAGAGAUCCUUCUACUGCCUGGUUGGAUUGCUCUGUCAGAGGACAGCGCCGUGGUACUGAGUCUCAUCGACACUAUUGACACCGUCAUGGGCCAUGUAUCCUCCAACCUGCACGGCAGCACGCCCCAGGUCACCGUGGAGGGCUCCUCUGCCAUGGCAGAGUUUUCCGUGGCCAAAAUCCUGCCCAAGACCGUGAAUUCCUCCCAUUACCGCUUCCCGGCCCACGGGCAGAGCUUCAUCCAGAUCCCCCACGAGGCCUUCCACAGGCACGCCUGGAGCACCGUCGUGGGUCUGCUGUACCACAGCAUGCACUACUACCUGAACAACAUCUGGCCCGCCCACACCAAGAUCGCGGAGGCCAUGCAUCACCAGGACUGCCUGCUGUUCGCCACCAGCCACCUGAUUUCCCUGGAGGUGUCCCCACCACCCACCCUGUCUCAGAACCUGUCGGGCUCUCCACUCAUUACGGUCCACCUCAAGCACAGAUUGACACGUAAGCAGCACAGUGAGGCCACCAACAGCAGCAACCGAGUCUUCGUGUACUGCGCCUUCCUGGACUUCAGCUCCGGAGAAGGGGUCUGGUCGAACCACGGCUGUGCGCUCACGAGAGGAAACCUCACCUACUCCGUCUGCCGCUGCACUCACCUCACCAACUUUGCCAUCCUCAUGCAGGUGGUCCCGCUGGAGCUUGCACGCGGACACCAGGUGGCGCUGUCGUCUAUCAGCUAUGUGGGCUGCUCCCUCUCCGUGCUCUGCCUGGUGGCCACGCUGGUCACCUUCGCCGUGCUGUCCUCCGUGAGCACCAUCCGGAACCAGCGCUACCACAUCCACGCCAACCUGUCCUUCGCCGUGCUGGUGGCCCAGGUCCUGCUGCUCAUUAGUUUCCGCCUCGAGCCGGGCACGACCCCCUGCCAAGUGAUGGCCGUGCUCCUACACUACUUCUUCCUGAGUGCCUUCGCAUGGAUGCUGGUGGAGGGGCUGCACCUCUACAGCAUGGUGAUCAAGGUCUUUGGGUCGGAGGACAGCAAGCACCGUUACUACUAUGGGAUGGGAUGGGGUUUUCCUCUUCUGAUCUGCAUCAUUUCACUGUCAUUUGCCAUGGACAGUUACGGAACAAGCAACAAUUGCUGGCUGUCGUUGGCGAGUGGCGCCAUCUGGGCCUUUGUAGCCCCUGCCCUGUUUGUCAUCGUGGUCAACAUUGGCAUCCUCAUCGCUGUGACCAGAGUCAUCUCACAGAUCAGCGCCGACAACUACAAGAUCCAUGGAGACCCCAGUGCCUUCAACCGAUUGCAGGUGACAGAAAUCCCAGCAUGCACUGGCCUAAGCAGAAGGGGGACUCACUGACGCAGCUGACUGUGAAGUCCGGAGCUCAGAAGCCCUGGCGUUGCAGGAAUUCUUUGGCAGUUGCAGCACCGGGCCCAGCUCGCCUUCGCAUCCUUAGUGUUGGCUUCAGGCCGAGGUCGACUCUGCCCCCUGGUGGCCGAAUGGCUGCGGCAGGGGUUCAGGCCCACGGGGGAGUCCCUGUCCCACCUGCUGAGACGGAGGCCUGCGCCUGGAGGACGAUGGGGACUCAGGCUGGACCUGUGCCCUCCCUGAGCCAGACCCUGUAGAGGGGGAUUCACUCAUAUGACCGUGUGACUGUUCAGUUAGCACCCCCAAACCACAGGGCUGAAAGCUGGGGAGGCUGUCCCUCGCAGGGAAUUCAGGGGCUUUGUGAAAAGCAGGGCGUGGGUACCAGGCAGCUGACAUUCUGUACUGUUACUUCAGCCACCGCGUAUCUGUUCUGAUGUGAAAGCAAAAGUGGCAAAUAUGUCAGCAGCGAAUCUAUGAGAGAAUUAGUCUGUAAUGAAUUCCAAACACCAUAAAUUAACCUGACAAGAGGCUGCAGCCUCCUUGGGCUGUUCAGCUCCUGGAAACCUUCAAGGGUUGUGCCCCGUGCGAGAAGAGAUGCUCGUGGGGUCAGAGAUCACGUCCUUUCCUCUUCCAUUGCUGAGACCAGGAUGGUCUCCUGGACCUCUCAUGGCCUGGCUGGGGAGGGACCUGUCCCUUCCUCACCCCAGCCCUCAGCUCCCCAGGCCCUCACCUCAGCGUUCAGGGUCAGCCAGUCUGUUGCCAGCUUGUCUCCAGCAAAAGCUCACAAUCCCCUGUCUGAGCCCCAUGAGGCCACUACUUCCACUGUCACCAGAACACCCCUGUGCACCUGCCCCGCACCUGUGCACCGCCUUCCAUCUCUACCCCACUGCGCCCCAUCCUCCCAUCAGUGCCCACCCAGGAAGCAGCUUCUGUCCACUGCCUUUGCUUCUCCAUGGAAAUGUCCUCCAAGCGACAGGCUGGCACUGUGUCUGCAGCUCUUGUGAAGGCUCGAGGUAGCGUGCCCCGGGAGAGCAUGCCCAGGUCUUUGCAGGGCACAGCUGAAGGCAUUGCCCAUCCUUCCCACCUGCGUCUGCACCUGGCAGCCCAGGGAUGCGUCCCUUCCGGGGAGGUGCAGGCAGGCAUCUCUGGGGACAGACCGCUCUGGGUCCCUCUCCAUUGUGCAACCCAGCACAUUUCCCAAUGCCUUCAGCUCCUCUCCUUUGGGCGGCCAGGUCUGCCCCUCAGGGAUGCUUCCUCACAAUCUUCUUAGUGUGGAUUGUGUAACACUUGACUCCCAGGGCUGAGGAAGCACAGCCAGGGAGCAGGCGCCAGGCAGGAAGAGGCAGUCACUGCAUCGUGAGGAAGCUUCCCCAGCACCUUGCUAUUCUUCAUCCUCUGGUUUUAUUCUAGUGAUUUUCUUAGUGCCAAGCAGCCCAGUACUCAGUGAAUAACAAGAUAAGAUUCUUCCUCAGGGGCCCUCCACAGGGUUGGCUUUCACUUCCCUGCCACCCCCCUACCCCAAGAAAAGUGGAGAAUAGAAUAAGUGAGGUCUGAGCAGGGGGAGAAGCCUGGCUUUCACUUUUUAAAAAAGUCUCUGUUUAUUGAUUGUGAUUCCAGACUCCUGAAAAAGAAGCAGAGAAUGGUCAGGUUUUACAAGUGGGACCCUGGGGGCGGGGGCGUGAGGGUGAGACCCCCACAGAAGUGCACCCACGAGCAGGUGGGCUGUGGGGCCUGGAGACUCAGGGCCUGAGCCCCCUAGGCCAGGGCCAACCUUGGGGGAGCAGAAGGGGGUCAUAGAUCAGAGAGGAAAGCACACCCCCUGCCUAGAGCCUCCUUCAGAUCCAGGGACCCCUCUUCUUCUGCUUUUGACCAGGGACACUGACAGCUCUGGCCGUGUUGAGAGUCCGCAGAGCUUCAGCUCAGCGUCUUCCCCCAAGAUCUUCUUCUAUUGUUCAUUUUAAGAAAAGUCAAACCAUCACUUUAAAAGUAGCACAUUUUGGUACUUAUUUCUCAGUGAUUGAUCCUUUCAGAUACGGUUUCCCGGGACCUAAAGAUUGUAGCUGAAUAAUGCAUGAUAUUGUUGUUUCCCAGAAACAGGUGUUUUAUUUUUAUUGCAUUAGCAUUAUGAGAACAAGCUGGCUGCGGCUUCUCUGAGAGCUGAAGUGCUGGAACACUUCUGGGUUUUACAGGCACCGGUUGCCCGGAGCUGUCAGUGCCAGGCUCUUGGUCUCUUGACAAGGAAGCUCAUUAUGGCCGCAUCUCACCUCCUCCGGGGAGGUGCCAGAUCUGUGUGCAGCACUGCUGCAUGGCCGUCCACUUGUUCAUCAUUCAUUCAUUCAUUCAUUCAUUCAAUGUUUAUUUCCUGAGAGCCUCUGAGUCCUGGUGCUGGGAUGCACUUUGGGGUUACAGAGACAAAAAGACCAAGCUCCAGCCUUUAAGGAACCCACAGUCUAUGAGGGAGACAAUCUCAGUCACUGGCCUGAGUGAUGAGGGGUAAACCGAGGCAUGUGACAGUGGCUGACCUGGGCAGCAGGAACUCCGCUAGUCUCUAGACUUUUCUCUAAAGCUCAAAGGCAGAAGGUCCCUGCUGUGGAAAGCCCAGCUGUUUCAGAAGUCAGGAUGGACUGGGCUUGAGGUAGUUGGCCAUGAUUGACACAGCACAUCAGGAAUGGCUUUGAGGCAGGCAGCUGGUGUGCCCAGUCAGAGCAGGUGCUAACUGGCCCAGGUGGGGACGUCUGCAUACCCUCUGGUUCUGCCCCUGAUGAAACCCUGUAUCACCUUAGCCAUUACCAGGGGCUGUGGGGCCUCAGUUUCCUUAUUAUACAAUGGGGUCAAUAUAUAACCUGCCUCUCCUGUGUCAAGAGGGCCCAUGGGCUCUAGGGAGAUAAAAACGCAUGCUGAUGGGGCUGGUGUGUUCAGCGAUGGGGCUCUGUCAGUUCACAGUGCAGUUCAGCAAGCCCUUGUUUAGCACGUCCUUUGAGCAUGAGCAGGGCCAUGAAGAUGACCACUUGGCCCUGCCCUCUGAGAACUCACCGUCAGUGUCACAGGAGGGCUCGGGUGAUCAGCGGGGGACACGCGGGCUGCAGCCCAGUGAGGCCUGGAGAAAUCUUCCUGGCCAUGGCCUCAUUUCAGGCCCAGGCCUCAUUGCACCCUUCCAAGCGUCUCACAGGAGGCCUGGGUUCUGGACGCUGCGGGGGAUGCUCUGCUGCUUCAGUCCCCCGAAUCUCUCCCCUCCGUCCUGGUUCCUCCUCAUCUUUGCAAACAGCUCAAAUGCAAGCCCUGGGCCUGGACAGAUUCUCCCUAUGGCCUAGGUGAGCCCUGGGUGCUACCUGAACUUUUCCAGAGCUCUCUCCCACCCACCAGCUGUAAGGGGAUGGAGGUGUGGAAACACCGAGGCUCCUCCCAGGUAAAUGCCUCAACCAGGGCUACCUGCAGGGAGGACCCCAGGUCUUGCUCCCGGCAGGGCGGUGCCUGCACCCAUCUGGAAGCCUGGCGUCUCGAGGGCAGUCCUCACAGCCUGCACCUGCCCUCCUGCCACUCAG